UGACAUUCUCUAAUCCUAGGAGGGAGAUAUCAUUAAAUCACUGGUCUGAUUUUUACUCCUACUUUGUUCCUAGUAGUGGGACCAUACAGAAGUGGGGCUACCCUGGACAUGAUGAUGACCUUUUUAGGGAAGACUAGAUGUGGCUUGUGUGGGAGGAGGGACAGUAACUGUAGAAGAAAAUUUAGAGACCAGUAUGACUUAGUACAGGCAAGGUAGACAGUUUUGCAACUUCAUGAAAGAAAGCGUGCUCUUAAUUCUGUAACCUAGGCAGGUUCUAAGUUUGACUUAAAAGAGGUGACAUCCUUGAUGCCAAGAGACCCAAGAAGAAGUUGGAAUGCAUUUCAGGUCCACAGUUUUAUGUGUGAGCAAGAUGGAGGCUGACCUGUCUGGCUUUAACAUCGAUGCCCCCCGUUGGGACCAGCGCACCUUCCUGGGGAGAGUGAAGCACUUCCUAAACAUCACGGACCCCCGCACUGUCUUUGUAUCUGAGCGGGAGCUGGACUGGGCCAAGGUGAUGGUGGAGAAGAGCAGGAUGGGGGUUGUGCCCCCAGGCACCCAAGUGGAGCAGCUGCUGUAUGCCAAGAAGCUGUAUGACUCGGCCUUCCACCCCGACACUGGGGAGAAGAUGAAUGUCAUCGGGCGCAUGUCUUUCCAGCUUCCUGGCGGCAUGAUCAUCACGGGCUUCAUGCUCCAGUUCUACAGGACGAUGCCGGCGGUGAUCUUCUGGCAGUGGGUGAACCAGUCCUUCAAUGCCUUAGUCAACUACACCAACAGGAAUGCGGCUUCCCCCACAUCAGUCAGGCAGAUGGCCCUUUCCUACUUCACAGCCACAACCACUGCUGUGGCCACGGCUGUGGGCAUGAACAUGUUGACAAAGAAAGCGCCGCCCUUGGUGGGCCGCUGGGUGCCCUUUGCCGCUGUGGCUGCGGCUAACUGUGUCAAUAUCCCCAUGAUGCGACAGCAGGAGCUCAUAAAGGGAAUCUGCGUGAAGGACAGGAAUGAAAAUGAGAUUGGUCAUUCCCGGAGAGCUGCGGCCAUAGGCAUCACCCAAGUAGUUAUUUCUCGGAUCACCAUGUCAGCUCCUGGGAUGAUCUUGCUGCCAGUCAUCAUGGAAAGGCUUGAGAAAUUGCACUUCAUGCAGAAAGUCAAGGUCCUGCACGCCCCAUUGCAGGUCAUGCUGAGCGGGUGCUUCCUCAUCUUCAUGGUGCCAGUGGCGUGUGGGCUUUUCCCACAGAAAUGUGAAUUGCCAGUUUCCUAUCUGGAACCGAAGCUCCAAGACACUAUCAAGGCCAAGUAUGGAGAACUUGAGCCUUAUGUCUACUUCAAUAAGGGUCUCUAAAUGCCCCACUUCAGCAAGGACCAGUCUAUUCCCAUAUUCACCAGCUCCUCCUUAGCUACGUGCACACUUGUGUCCUCCUUCCCCUUUGCCAACAAGGCCUGAAGGCCAGGGUAGAUUGGGGGGUGGGACAAUGAAUGCCUCAUACUUACACCCUGGUACUGGUUGAUUGGACCUCAGGGGAAAAAAGUGAAAAAGGGUAGCAAAGGCCAAUGUCUUCUAGCUGCUUCCUCAACCCCUGUCCCCUGGAGACCAGAAGCUGAGGCCCUCUCAGGGAGGAGACAUCCAAGCAAAUCAUUUGGAAAAGUUAGGAAACCUUUAGGAUUCUGGUUCCAGCCAGGGUUGAGGAAAAGACCUUGGAUCAAAAGGAAGCUUCUAUACCUCUUUCUUCUUCGCUUCCUCCUCUCCCAAGCAAUGGAAACUUUUACCCAUGUAAUUCUAGCUGAACUCAGGAAAAAGAAGGGGGAAAGGACUCUGUCCCCUUGGGGCUCAUCACCCUUCCACAUCCUCCUCCUCGUUGCCCCCUGGUCAGGCAGCUUCUUUUUUUUUUUUUUCAAGAUGGAGUCUUGCUCUGUCGCCCAGGCUGGAAUGCAGUGGCGCGAUCUCGGCUCACUGCAAACUCUGCCUCCUGGAUUCAAGCGAUUCUCCUGCCUCAGCCUCUCAAGUAGCUGGGAUUACAGGGCACCUGCCACCACGCCUGGCUAAUUUUUGUAUUUUAGUGGAGACGGGGUUUCACCAUGCUGGCCAGACUGGUCUCGAACUCCUGACCUCAGGUGAUCCGCCCGCCUCAGCCUCUGAAAUUGCUGGGAUUACAGGCAUGAGCCACCACACCCAGCCCGGACAGCUUCUUUGGGAGUGCUGCUAACCUUGAAAUUAUCAGACACUUAGGAGUUAUUAGUGCUAAAAAGGGGACCGUGCAAGGCAGCAGAGUUACAUGGUUCUUCAAAUCAUGUCUGAACCUAUUCUUGGAAUCUUCUCUAUAAUAAGGGAAGUUCUCUUACCCCACUGCCACAUACCUCUGUUUUAAAAGAUAAGUCCACUAACUGUGAGUAAAAAUGAUAUAUAUAGGCAUUAACCACACACUUUAAUGGGUAUAAUUUCCUGGCUGCCUCCCUUCCUCAGCCCAUUAGGUUAAACACCAAAGAAAGACUGGUGUGUACUGAAUAGGAAAGGGAAGUUUUAUUUGGAACCUUCUAAGAGGAAAUCAACCAGGACCAAAGAGCCUUAAAGGACACACAGCAAUGCACAGCCACUUCCCUUCCCCAGCUUGGCUGCCCUAGGUGAUUUCUCAAGCUCCUUGGGGGACUGUUGUUUCUCAUCUGGAAUCAAUGUGUGUAUGAGUUUUGUCUGGUAGGAUUGCUGACUCUGUCCAACAGAUAUCACUGUGAAUUGAAUAAAUUUGUUGAAAGAGCACACAGGCACACAUACACACAAACUGUAAACUAAGUUAAUGAAGCCUGAAUGGAAAGCAGGAUCUGGCCUUACUUUGGCCUUGGCAUGUCAGAAGGUAUCACAACUACUAUAUAAGGGGAACUUGUCUGAUGCCUGGAGGCUGUUGUUUAUUUCCCUCAUUAAAGGGGAAAUCCACCUGUCUCCACAGGAAGCUCCAGAUCUCCCAGAAUGGGAGCUGUGUUGCCCUAGAGCAAGAGUUGGCAAGCUAUGGCUCAAGGGGCCAAAUCCACCUGCCACCUGUUUUUGUGCAAUUGGAAGCUAAGAAUGUUUUUACAUUUUUAAAGAGUUGUAAAAGGGAACAACAGGAAUGACAGAGACCCUACCUAUGUGGCAUACAAAGCCUAAAAUAUUUACUGUCUGAUCCUUGACACAAAAAGUUUCCCCUGCCCUGGAGCAGUGGUUCUUAAGCACAUGCAUCAACCGGGCGCAGUGGCUCAUGCCUGUAAUCCCCACACUUUGGGAGGCCGAGGCAGGUGGAUCACCUGAGGUCAGGAGUUCGAGACCAGCCUGAUCAACAUGGUGAAACCCGAUCUCUACUAAAAAUACAAAAAAUUUGCUGGGUGUGGUGGCAUACACCUGUAAUCCCAGCUACUCGGGGGGCUGAGACUGGAGAAUCACUUGAACCUGGGAGGUGGAGGUUGUGGUGAGCCAAGAUUGCGCCACUGCACUCCAACCUGGGCGACUCCGUCUCAAAAAAAAAAAAGAAAACACAUCAGAAUUAGCUGGCAGGCUUGUUAAAGCACAGAUUGCAGGAUCCAUUGCCAGAUUCUGUCACUCUGGGCUGGAGCCUGAGAACGUGCAUUUCUAGUCAUUGCCCGGUGAUGCUGAUUCUGUUGGUCUUGGCACCAUACGUGGAGGAGCACUGCUCUAAGGGGAAAGGGCCUCCUCCCCGAGGCCAAGGAAUUCACUGCAACUUGAUUUUUCUCCCCGUUUAAAAAAGUUAAAAUAUAACUCACAUACCAUAAACUUAGUCCUUUUAAAGUGUACAAUUCAGUGGUUUUUAAUGUAGUCACAAAGUUGUACAAGCAUCACCACUAAUUCCAGAAUUAUUUUGAGACAGGAUCUCACUCUGUUACCCUGGUUGGAGUGCAGUAGUGCAAUCACUGCUCAUUGCAGCCUCAACCUCCUGAGCUCAAGUAAUCCUCCUGCCUCAGCCUCUGGGGUAGCUGGGACCACAGGCUAAUUUGAUUUUUUUGAUGAGGUCUCACUAUGUUGCCCCAGGCUGGUCUCGAACUCAUGGCCUCAAGUGAUCCUCCUCCCUCAGCCUUCCAAAGUGUUGGAAUUACACACAUGAGCCACUGCAUCUGGUCUCAGAACAUUUUUCUUAGCCCCAAAAGAAACCCCAUACCCAUUGGCAGUCACUCCACAUUCUCCCUACCUGCCAGCGCCUCACAAUUCACUUCCUGUCUUUAGAGAUUUGCGUAUUCUGAACAUUUCAUGUAAGUGGAGUAAUGCAGUAUGUGGCCCUCUGUGUCUGGUUUCUUUCCUUAGGAUAAUGUUUUCAAGGUUCAUCCAUGUUGUAGCAUAUGCAAUUUGAUUUUAGCUGGUGUCUGAACAGAAAAGUCUGUCUUUGAGCUAGCUUCUUUAGGACAGGAGACCUGGCUUUAUUUCCAAAAGCAAAUAGGAAAAGGGAAACAUUACCAGAGCCAGUAGAGCUUGGAAACAACUCCUGACUGAUGUUCUUUCAGAACAUACAAUGUUUCCCCUUCCUUCUCAGCUCCUCAAGCCUCUUGGAUUUCCUGUUCUCUUAUAGACAACUGCUCUUUUGGAAAUGUCUGGAAGGUAUGUGGUGGCUAUAAUGUUCAGGGACAUUCUAAAAAGUGGUCACUCAAACUGCAUCUCAGUCUCAUUUUGUAACAUCUCUCUUCUUUGAGUUGGCUGCUGUGGGAUGUUGAAUAAGAGGCAGUUAAGGUUACUAAAAGGCCUUGGUGUGGGAAGUGCUAAUCCAGACUGUCCUAUCCAAUAGCUCAGCUUGAGCUUUCAGGUAAAAGGAGAAAGGGAAGUUGGGGCAAAAUCCCCUGUGUUUGCCAAACUGAAUUGGGGUUUCUUAUUUAUUGAGAGAAAGAGGGUAUCACUUUCUUGCCCAGGCUGGAGUGCAAUGGUAUGAUCAUGACUCAUUGCUUCCUCAGCCUCCUGGACUCAAGUGAUCCUCCUGCCUUAGCCUCCCGAGUAGCUUCUUUUUCCUGAGUUCGGCUAGAAUAGCAUGGGUAAAAGGUUCCAUUGCUCGGGAGAGGAGGAGGAAGGGAAGAAGAAGAGGUAUAGAAGCUUCCUUUUGAUCCAAGGUCUUUUCCUCAAUCCUGGCUAGAACCAGAAUCCUAAAGGUUUCCUGACUACAGGUACAUGCCACCAUGCCCAGCUAAUUUUUAAAUUUUUUGUAGACAGAGGGCCUCACUAUGUUUCCCAGGUUGGUCUUGAACCCCUGACCUCAAGCAAUCCUCAUGCCUUGGCCUCCCAAAGUGUUGGGAUUACAGGCGUGAGCCACUACAUCCCACCUGGGGUUUCUUAGUGAUGAUGAAACCUAGCCUUUAUGUGGAAGACUUACAACUUUUUGAGGCCAGGAAUUAGAGACCUUGUGCCAUGAAAAUAAUUUGGUCCUUCCCUAGUACUCAAUUUUUACUUCUCCUCUAAGGAGCUUGACUUGUGGAAUGGAUAAAUUUCUAAGAAACGAGAGAUUGGCAAAAAUACGUGUCACUUUUUAUAGUACUUGGAAAAGCAGGAUCAAGAUAAAGGCAGAACUAUGGACUUUCUUAAGCUGAGGGAAGACUGACUUAACUCUUACCUGUUUCCCAUUUUUCCAACACUUAAGCCAAGAACAACUUCCUCUGGGCUCAGAUGUGGGCUAGACUGGGCCAGGCUGUAAAACACUUUGACAGGUUUUUGAGAGGAAAUUGACUGCUAAAGUCAACUGUGUUAUUUGCCAUGGGUCUUCCUUUGUCCAUUUAUUUUACCAACUUUUUUUUUUCUUUUUUUUUUGAGACAGAGUCUCACUCUGUCACCUAGGGUGGAGUGCAGUGGCACAGUCUUGGCUCACUGCAACCUCUGCCUCCCAGGUUCAAGCGAUUCUUCUGCUUUAGCCUCCUGAGUAGCUGGGACUACAGGCAUGCACCACCACGCCUGGCUAAUUUUUUGUAUUUUUAGUAGAGAUUGGGUUUCACAAUGUUGGCCAGGCUCGAACUCCUGACCAUGUGAUCCGCCCACCUCGGCCUCCCAAAGUGCUGGGAUUACAGGCAGGAGCCACCGCACCUGGCCUUUUUUUUUUUUUGAGACAGGGUCUCACUCUGUUGCCCAGGCUGGAGUACAGUGGCACAAUCAAGGCUCAUUGCAGCUUCAAUCUCCCUAGCUCUGGUGAUUGUCCCACCUCAGCCUCCCAAGUAGCUGGGACUACAAGUGUGCACCACCAUGCUUGGCUAAUUUGGCUAAUUUAGUUUUUUUAUUUUUGUAGAGACAGGGUUCUCUCCAUGUUGCCCAGGCUGGUUUCAAACUCCUGAGCUCAAGGGAUCUACCUGCCUCAGCCUCCCAAAGGGCUAGGAUUAUAAGCAUGAGCCACCACACCUGGCUAUUUUACCAACAUUGAUCAAGCUCUGGUUGAGCCUUGUACAGGAUAUUAUAGGCUUUAAAAGAAGAAGAAGAAAGACCUGGUAUGCUGUACAAAAAACUGCAAACCAGGCACGCAGAUAUAAGUGUUACAAGAAUCCAGAAGAAGCAGCAAGGAGAUGGGGCUAGGAGUUUGUAAGCAGGGAACUGUAUCUGUAAUAUGUAAAUGAAGUUACUGGGCAUCUCUUCAAUGGUCAGUGUGAGUGGAAUGUGUGGGAAAAUGUAGUGGUGAGAGGUGAGAUAAAGAGAAGUAGACAGGGACGAAGUCACAGAGAGGACCGUGUUGGGAAGUUUGGACUCUCUAUUCUGUAGGUAGAUGAAGUAUUUAAAAGAAGAGGCCAUGAUAUAGUAAUAUUUGGUUUAAUGUGGUAUGGUUGUAGUGUGUGGCGGAAAUUUGAGAGGAAGAAUUGUCAACUUGCAGGGCAGCAGGGAAGCCAUUUGUAUUUAGCUAGAAGAACAUGGAUUGAAGCAAUGGAUGAUGGAUUUCAGAGCAAUUUGUGAAGUAGAACCAGAAUUUUGUCCGUCGAACUUGGGGUGACGAAGCACUAUGCCUCAGAUAAAGGUACUAUCUUCUAGGGAAUUCAAACGGACCUAAGCUGCUAUUUGGGCAGUUGAGACCAAGAGAGGCAUCCUGGUAAUAGUGCUGUGCUUCAAGACAAAAGACAUUAAAAUAUUUUUACAUUGCAA